ACUCCCGCAUGGUAGCUGGAGCAGCAAACAACUGCUUAGGGAUUUGAAGCCAGGUGUCCUAACUUCCUCCAUGGGCGCUCAGCCUGGGGAACCUCAGAACACUUGCUCUAGGAUCCAGACACUGUUUAGGAGGGUCAAGACCUUACUCAUCAAAGCCCCGCCUCCCCCCCAACCUCCGCCUCCACCCCCAUCCUGGAACCCUGGCUGUACACACGUGUAUGGGUACGCGUUUGGCCACAUGCAUGACAACAACCUUGAACAUCUCCCGUCACAGCAGGUACUGGACACAGGAGAGCAGCUGAUGGUCCCCGUGGAAGUCCUGGAAGUGGAUAACAAGGAGGCCUUGUGGAAGUUUCUACUCUCAGGAGCUAUGGCCGGGGCGGUGUCUCGCACGGGCACGGCACCUCUGGACAGAGCCAAGGUGUACAUGCAGCUACUCGGGAGGCUGAGGCAGGAGAAUCGCCUGAACCUGGGAGGCGGAGGUUGCAGUGAGCCGAGAUCCCCCGACCGCACUCCAGCCUGGGCGACAGAGUCUACUCCUCCAAGACGAACUUCACCAACCUGCUGGGGGGGCUACAGAGCAUGGUCCAGGAGGGCGGCUUCCGCUCCCUGUGGCGGGGCAACGGCAUCAACGUGCUCAAGAUUGCUCCUGAGUAUGCCAUCAAGUUCUCCGUAUUCGAGCAGUGCAAGAAUUACUUCUGUGGAAUACAAGGGUCCCCGCCCUUCCAGGAGCGUCUCCUUGCUGGCUCCCUGGCUGUGGCCAUCUCCCAGACCCUCAUCAACCCCAUGGAGGUGCUGAAGACGCGGUUGACCUUGCGUCGGACGGGCCAGUACAAGGGGCUGCUGGACUGCGCCAGGCAGAUCUUGCAGCGAGAGGGCACCCGCGCCCUUUACCGCGGCUACCUGCCCAAUAUGCUCGGCAUCAUCCCCUAUGCCUGCACCGACCUGGCUGUCUAUGAGAUGCUCCAGUGCUUCUGGGUGAAGUCAGGCAGGGAUAUGGGGGACCCCAGUGGCCUGGUCAGUCUGUCGUCUGUGACGCUAUCCACGACCUGUGGCCAGAUGGCCAGCUACCCACUGACUCUGGUGCGCACCAGGAUGCAGGCCCAAGAUACCGUGGAGGGCUCAAAUCCCACCAUGCGCGGAGUCCUCCAGCGGAUCCUGGCCCAGCAGGGCUGGCUAGGGCUGUACCGAGGCAUGACCCCCACGCUACUGAAGGUCUUACCAGCAGGUGGCAUCAGCUAUGUGGUGUACGAAGCCAUGAAGAAAACCCUGGGCAUAUAGGCUGUGAGCUGGACGACACAGCCUAGGCAGAAAUGGGACAGGAGGACCUGAUGACCCCUGGCCCCAAAGAGCCCUCGAGGCCUCAAGGUUCAGGCCCUGGGGCAGUUUUUGGUGGCAAAAGCAGGCUGGGGGUGGGGGUGGGGCUCUGGGUCAGAAGAUUCCUGAAGCUGGGGUUGGUGGUGGGUGGAGGGGGGCAGUGCUGGGUCAGAAAACUCCUGGGACUCCCUCCCCAGGGUGCAGCCUGAGACAAGAAACGUGGACUCCAGUCUGGCCCCUUGUGGGUCGUCCUGGCUCCAGGGCGAAAUGGUGAACAUGUCACACAACAAGGAAUAAAGAGAUGGUUUUUGCUGAA